GCAGACUGCUCUGGCAGCCGGAGAGGAGGCGGUGCGGCGGUGGCGCUGCGGAGACCCGGUCCAGACGCCUGGCGGCCGCCGGCACACAAGGCGCUUUCUAGCUCCCUCCCCCGAGCGCACAGCCCGCCUCCUUCCGCGGCGCCUGCAGUGGCAGGCUUGCUCUGCCCUACCGUGACGCGCUCCGGAGACGCUCUGCGGGUCCUGGACACCGGGUCCGCGGCGUGGGGACGACAGACGGAGGCGAACGCCAUCGGUAGCCGGUCCGCGAGCCAUCGUUCGGGGCGCAGUCCUCUCCCCGGCUGGCCCUCCUUUCUCCGGGGCAUUCGCCACCGCUUCCCUGGGCUGAGACGACCGGUUCGUCGCCUCCUUGCCCGUGACCGUCGCUAGAACUCAGUUGUGCGUUGCGGCCAGUCGCCACUGCUGUGUCAGCAUUUGCAGGUAUACAGGAACAGUCCUAGUGAUGCACUAUUUAAUCAAAAGACGGAUGGAUCUUUUGUUCUUGCAGCUGGUUUUCCAAGAAUUGAUAUAAAGCGGGAAGAACAGAAAACAGCAGUCAUAAGUAUGCUACUCAAAAUAUUCUUCUUUUUAUGUGCCAAAUCCUCACAUUGGAAGCUGUCCCGAGCAAGACAGGAGUGGAAACAAAAUGUCAGUCAGUGUGCAUGAGAACCGCAAGUCCAGGGCCAGCAGCGGCUCCAUUAACAUCUAUCUGUUUCACAAGUCCUCCUACGCUGACAGCGUCCUCACUCACCUGAAUCUUUUACGCCAGCAGCGUCUCUUCACUGACGUCCUUCUCCAUGCCGGAAAUAGGACCUUCCCUUGCCACCGGGCAGUGCUGGCUGCAUGCAGUCGCUACUUUGAGGCCAUGUUCAGUGGUGGCCUGAAAGAGAGCCAGGACAGUGAGGUCAACUUUGACAAUUCCAUCCACCCAGAAGUCUUGGAGCUGCUGCUUGACUAUGCGUACUCCUCCCGGGUCAUCAUCAAUGAAGAAAAUGCAGAAUCGCUCCUGGAAGCUGGUGACAUGCUGGAGUUUCAAGACAUCCGGGAUGCAUGUGCAGAGUUCCUGGAAAAGAACCUGCAUCCCACCAACUGCCUGGGCAUGCUGCUGCUGUCUGAUGCACACCAGUGCACCAAGCUGUACGAACUAUCUUGGAGAAUGUGUCUCAGCAACUUCCAAACCAUCAGGAAGAAUGAAGAUUUCCUCCAGCUGCCCCAGGACAUGGUAGUGCAACUCUUGUCCAGUGAAGAGCUGGAGACAGAGGAUGAAAGGCUUGUGUACGAGUCUGCAAUUAACUGGAUCAGCUAUGACCUGAAGAAGCGCUAUUGCUACCUCCCAGAACUGUUGCAGACAGUAAGGCUGGCACUUCUGCCAGCCAUCUAUCUCAUGGAGAAUGUGGCCAUGGAGGAACUCAUCACCAAGCAGAGAAAGAGUAAGGAAAUUGUGGAAGAGGCCAUCAGGUGCAAACUGAAAAUCCUGCAGAAUGACGGUGUGGUAACCAGCCUCUGUGCCCGACCUCGGAAAACUGGCCAUGCCCUCUUCCUUCUGGGAGGACAGACUUUCAUGUGUGACAAGUUGUAUCUGGUAGACCAGAAGGCCAAAGAAAUCAUUCCCAAGGCUGACAUUCCCAGCCCAAGAAAAGAGUUUAGUGCAUGUGCGAUUGGCUGCAAAGUGUACAUUACUGGGGGGCGGGGGUCUGAAAAUGGGGUCUCAAAAGAUGUCUGGGUUUAUGAUACCCUGCACGAGGAGUGGUCCAAGGCUGCCCCCAUGCUGGUGGCCAGGUUUGGCCAUGGCUCUGCUGAACUGAAGCACUGCCUGUAUGUGGUUGGGGGGCACACGGCCGCAACUGGCUGCCUCCCGGCCUCCCCCUCAGUCUCUCUAAAGCAGGUAGAACAUUAUGACCCCACAAUCAACAAAUGGACCAUGGUGGCCCCACUCCGAGAAGGCGUUAGCAACGCCGCAGUAGUGAGUGCCAAACUUAAGUUAUUUGCUUUCGGAGGUACCAGUGUCAGUCAUGACAAGCUCCCCAAAGUUCAGUGUUACGAUCAGUGUGAAAACAGGUGGACUGUACCGGCCACCUGUCCCCAGCCCUGGCGUUACACAGCAGCAGCUGUGCUGGGGAACCAGAUUUUUAUUAUGGGGGGUGAUACAGAAUUCUCUGCCUGCUCUGCUUAUAAAUUCAACAGUGAGACUUACCAGUGGACCAAGGUGGGAGAUGUGACAGCAAAGCGCAUGAGCUGCCAUGCUGUGGCCUCUGGAAACAAACUCUACGUGGUUGGAGGAUACUUUGGCAUUCAGCGAUGCAAGACUUUGGACUGCUACGAUCCAACAUUAGACGUGUGGAACAGCAUCACCACUGUCCCGUACUCGCUGAUUCCUACUGCAUUUGUCAGCACCUGGAAACAUCUGCCUUCUUAAAUGCAGUACAUUCUAAAGAGAGUGAGCAUGAGCUCACUCCAUCACUCGAUGAGAUAAUAUGAGAUUUCUACUUCGGAGAGGCCAAGUCUAAUGAAGAGAAAAAAAGGAAAAGAAGUUGCAAGACUCGAAUAAAAUCUGCUGCACCUUGUAAAUGCUCUAACUGGACAUGAAGGAAAGGGGCGAGGGAGGGGGGUGGGAUUUUUGGUGCAAGUAGCACAUGGUUUAAAUAUGAAUGAACAAACCUGUGAUCUAGUCCUUGUCUUGUAAUUGUGGAUUAAUGUCAAUGUUAAUCAGCCCCUCAAAGGGAGAGAAAAGCUGGACCUUUUCCCUUGCUGUACCAUAUUCAGCAUUUGAUUUCCAUGGGCCCCACCAUUUAUGUGUAGAAUUUGAAAUGGUUGUCACCUCUCUCUGAGGACAGAGCUUGAAGCCUCCACACCAGCUGCUGCUGGAGAUUCAAAGCCCAACUGUGGGUCCGAGAGGGAAGCUGGCUGGGCUGGCUGAAGAAUGAAGACCACUGGACUCUCCGUUAAUCUCUAAGGGGUCUGCUCCCCAGGAACGUUUCUGAACAAUGGGGACUUUGUUGGUAGCCAUUUGGUAGAUGUUCUUUUCUAUUUAUAAGUGACUUUAAACUUUCCCUUGGCUGUUAAGAAGUUUGUUAUAGAUUUAGCUAUUUAUUGUUCGAUGCCUGCAUGCUGAAACAAUGCCUACAGCUGUCUUCACAUGUAUGGACGUGUGUGAAUGGUUGUACGUUUUGCACAUUUUGUGGCUGUUGAGAUGUGCUUUGCUGCACAAACAUGAAAAUUUUUGAGUUACAAUUUGGAGCAUAACUGGAGGGUGGGUUGGGGAGGGGUGGAUUUUUAAAAUGUCAAGACAGGGAAGGAUGACAAAAUGGAAAUUUAAAUGACAUCCUAGAGGUAGAGAAACCGUGGAGAUCGCUUUUCUCAGACUCACCAACUUUUAAUGGGAUUUCAUGGGGUUUGGUUGUGCUGAUAGGGUAAGGGGAGGCUGCUUUCUGCCCUUCUCCCCACUCCCAUCUGAUUUACUUAAUUCAGUCUCAGCUGCUGAAAUUUGGAAAGGACCAAAUUGCUUUACAGUUUUUUUCUUUGUGUAGUAUCUUGAAAUCCUGGAAAAUUCUAUGGAAUAGUUCUGUAUAUAGGGCACAAGUAAAGGCAUUGUCCAAAGUUUAUUUAUUUAUUUAUUACCCUAAGAAUGCUUUGCCAUAACCACAUUUAAUGGGAAAAACGGCAGUAUCACAGAUGUAAAUUAACUCACCAGAUUUACUGGGCCUGAACUCAUUCUCUUCUUGCUAUAUGAUUUAGCAAGUUCUAGAAGGUCUCCAAGACAAUAAUUACAUUGGCACAAUGUAUACUUCAGUGCUCACCCGUAGGCAAAUCUCUUUUUAAAAAACUCUUUGGUGCACAAGUAACACAUUUGGCCACAAAACACCAAAGAAUUGUAGGCAGUGGCCCCUAUUGAGAAGUUUUCCGGUAGAGUUGGAAAUCAGUUGUGAAUACAUUCUUUGCUAGUUGGAGUGCUUGUUUACUAAGCAUGUGCCGUCGUAGGUAUUAGUGCUAGUCUCAGAUAGGUGCUUCCCCUGAGGUGCAGGGGAAGACCAAAGUUUGCAACUCGAACUGCUUUCGUCCAUGUUUCUCACAUUGCUGUAUUUUAGAAAAUAGGGGUUAAGACUGAUAACAACCUUUUACAUUGUGACUGUGUUUGCAUUGUCUAAUGACAGAUAAAUCCUUAACAUUUCUCUCCACCUUAGUACUUUAGACUAAUUGUGUUUGUCCGUCCAUGCCAUGAAUGAGUGGGCUGUAGUUGGGCCUAAAUAAAUGAGCUGUUGGAAGAAAAGAAUCACAGUACUUUCCAGCAGUCAGUCCCUGGUUCCUAGAUGUGUUCUAAGCAAUGCAAAUGUCUAAUUGUCCCCCAGUGGGCAUAGUCAGUGUCGUUUAUAUUGUAGCAGUUACAGCUCUGUAGUUUAUGAUGCAAAUCUGCCAAGAGAGAUGUAUGUGUCACUGCAUGGCUUCUGAAAGCAGGAUGAAUUUUCUGCAGCUGUUUCAAAGUUGGGGUCUGUUCUUGAAUCCUCUAUUAAUUACUGUGUGUGAGCCAGAGGGAGCUGUGGUAAGGGUUGGGCCCCCAGCCUGUAGGGAACUUUCUGGACUCCCACUCUUUGAAUCGAUAUAGGCAUUUGGUCUCACUACUUGACCAUUCUCACCCUGUGAAACGUCCCACACUUUGAAGCAAAUACAAUUCACAGCACAGUACACACAAAAACCUUGGCAUAAGACAGAGAAGGUUCUUCUUAUUUUGUGGGCUGGUUGCUGUAGAAACACAUAACAAAGGGCAGCCCUCCACUUCUGGUAUAAUUGUGUAGCCCCUUUUCUUUGGGCUUGACACCUGUCUUGAAUAAGAGUGAUUAGAGCUGCAUAAUGUCCCUCUCUUGGCUAUUGACCAUGUGGUUCACGUACAAAACUCUGUAUAAGUUGAAGGAAAAUGUUCAUGUUCAUAUGUACUUGUUUGCUAUGACUACAUUUUGAGGUUUUGUAAAACUGUUAUUUUUUUUUUUUUCACAAUGUGAAACUGAAGGUCAAUAAAUUAUUAGAGAUUUUCUCUUCA